AGACGGUGAUAGCGAGCCACGCAUUCACAGGGCCACUGCUGCUCACAGAAGCAGUGAGGAUGAUGCCAGGAUGAUGUCUGCCUCGCGCCUGGCUGGGACUCUGAUCCCAGCCAUGGCCUUCCUCUCCUGCGUGAGACCAGAAAGCUGGGAGCCCUGCGUGGAGACUUGGCCCUAAACCACACAGAAGAGCUGGCAUGAAACCCAGAGCUUUCAGACUCCGGAGCCUCAGCCCUUCACCCCGAUUCCAUUGCUUCUUGCUAAAUGCUGCCGUUUUAUCACGGAGGUGGUUCCUAAUAUUACUUAUCAAUGCAUGGAGCUGAAUUUCUACAAAAUCCCCGACAACCUCCCCUUCUCAACCAAGAACCUGGACCUGAGCUUUAAUCCCCUGAGGCAUUUAGGCAGCUAUAGCUUCUUCAGUUUCCCAGAACUGCAGGUGCUGGAUUUAUCCAGGUGUGAAAUCCAGACAAUUGAAGAUGGGGCAUAUCAGAGCCUAAGCCACCUCUCUACCUUAAUAUUGACAGGAAACCCCAUCCAGAGUUUAGCCCUGGGAGCCUUUUCUGGACUAUCAAGUUUACAGAAGCUGGUGGCUGUGGAGACAAAUCUAGCAUCUCUAGAGAACUUCCCCAUUGGACAUCUCAAAACUUUGAAAGAACUUAAUGUGGCUCACAAUCUUAUCCAAUCUUUCAAAUUACCUGAGUAUUUUUCUAAUCUGACCAAUCUAGAGCACUUGGACCUUUCCAGCAACAAGAUUCAAAGUAUUUAUUGCACAGACUUGCGGGUUCUACAUCAAAUGCCCCUACUCAAUCUCUCUUUAGACCUGUCCCUGAACCCUAUGAACUUUAUCCAACCAGGUGCAUUUAAAGAAAUUAGGCUUCAUAAGCUGACUUUAAGAAAUAAUUUUGAUAGUUUAAAUGUAAUGAAAACUUGUAUUCAAGGUCUGGCUGGUUUAGAAGUCCAUCGUUUGGUUCUGGGAGAAUUUAGAAAUGAAGGAAACUUGGAAAAGUUUGACAAAUCUGCUCUAGAGGGCCUGUGCAAUUUGACCAUUGAAGAAUUCCGAUUAGCAUACUUAGACUACUACCUCGAUGAUAUUAUUGACUUAUUUAAUUGUUUGACAAAUGUUUCUUCAUUUUCCCUGGUGAGUGUGACUAUUGAAAGGGUAAAAGACUUUUCUUAUAAUUUCGGAUGGCAACAUUUAGAAUUAGUUAACUGUAAAUUUGGACAGUUUCCCACAUUGAAACUCAAAUCUCUCAAAAGGCUUACUUUCACUUCCAACAAAGGUGGGAAUGCUUUUUCAGAAGUUGAUCUACCAAGCCUUGAGUUUCUAGAUCUCAGUAGAAAUGGCUUGAGUUUCAAAGGUUGCUGUUCUCAAAGUGAUUUUGGGACAACCAGCCUAAAGUAUUUAGAUCUGAGCUUCAAUGGUGUUAUUACCAUGAGUUCAAACUUCUUGGGCUUAGAACAACUAGAACAUCUGGAUUUCCAGCAUUCCAAUUUGAAACAAAUGAGUGAGUUUUCAGUAUUCCUAUCACUCAGAAACCUCAUUUACCUUGACAUUUCUCAUACUCACACCAGAGUUGCUUUCAAUGGCAUCUUCAAUGGCUUGUCCAGUCUCGAAGUCUUGAAAAUGGCUGGCAAUUCUUUCCAGGAAAACUUCCUUCCAGAUAUCUUCACAGAGCUGAGAAACUUGACCUUCCUGGACCUCUCUCAGUGUCAACUGGAGCAGUUGUCUCCAACAGCAUUUAACUCACUCUCCAGUCUUCAGGUACUAAAUAUGAGCCACAACAACUUCUUUUCAUUGGAUACGUUUCCUUAUAAGUGUCUGAACUCCCUCCAGGUUCUUGAUUACAGUCUCAAUCACAUAAUGACUUCCAAAAAACAGGAACUACAGCAUUUUCCAAGUAGUCUAGCUUUCUUAAAUCUUACUCAGAAUGACUUUGCUUGUACUUGUGAACACCAGAGUUUCCUGCAAUGGAUCAAGGACCAGAGGCAGCUCUUGGUGGAAGUUGAACGAAUGGAAUGUGCAACACCUUCAGAUAAGCAGGGCAUGCCUGUGCUGAGUUUGAAUAUCACCUGUCAGAUGAAUAAGACCAUCAUUGGUGUGUCGGUCCUCAGUGUGCUUGUAGUAUCUGUUGUAGCAGUUCUGGUCUAUAAGUUCUAUUUUCACCUGAUGCUUCUUGCUGGCUGCAUAAAGUAUGGUAGAGGUGAAAACAUCUAUGAUGCCUUUGUUAUCUACUCAAGCCAGGAUGAGGACUGGGUAAGGAAUGAGCUAGUAAAGAAUUUAGAAGAAGGGGUGCCUCCAUUUCAGCUCUGCCUUCACUACAGAGACUUUAUUCCCGGUGUGGCCAUUGCUGCCAACAUCAUCCAUGAAGGUUUCCAUAAAAGCCGAAAGGUGAUUGUUGUGGUGUCCCAGCACUUCAUCCAGAGCCGCUGGUGUAUCUUUGAAUAUGAGAUUGCUCAGACCUGGCAGUUUCUGAGCAGUCGUGCUGGUAUCAUCUUCAUUGUCCUGCAGAAGGUGGAGAAGACCCUGCUCAGGCAGCAGGUGGAGCUGUACCGCCUUCUCAGCAGGAACACUUACCUGGAGUGGGAGGACAGUGUCCUGGGGCGGCACAUCUUCUGGAGACGACUCAGAAAAGCCCUGCUGGAUGGUAAAUCAUGGAAUCCAGAAGGAACAGUGGGUACAGGAUGCAAUUGGCAGGAAGCAACAUCUAUCUGAAGAGGAAAAAUAAAAACCUCCUGAGGCAUUUCUUGCCCAGCUGGGUCCAACACUUGUUCAGUUAAUAAGUAUUAAAUGCUGCCACAUGUCAGGCCUUAUGCUAAGGGUGAGUAAUUCCAUGGUGCACUAGAUAUGCAGGGCUGCUAAUCUCAAGGAGCUUCCAGUGCAGAGGGAAUAAAUGCUAGACUAAAAUACAGAGUCUUCCAGGUGGGCAUUUCAACCAACUCAGUCAAGGAACCCAUGACAAAGAAAGUCAUUUCAACUCUUACCUCAUCAAGUUGAAUAAAGACAGAGAAAACAGAAAGAGACAUUGUUCUUUUCCUGAGUCUUUUGAAUGGAAAUUGUAUUAUGUUAUAGCCAUCAUAAAACCAUUUUGGUAGUUUUGACUGAACUGGGUGUUCACUUUUUCCUUUUUGAUUGAAUACAAUUUAAAUUCUACUUGAUGACUGCAGUCGUCAAGGGGCUCCUGAUGCAAGAUGCCCCUUCCAUUUUAAGUCUGUCUCCUUACAGAGGUUAAAGUCUAGUGGCUAAUUCCUAAGGAAACCUGAUUAACACAUGCUCACAACCAUCCUGGUCAUUCUCGAGCAUGUUCUAUUUUUUAACUAAUCACCCCUGAUAUAUUUUUAUUUUUAUAUAUCCAGUUUUCAUUUUUUUACGUCUUGCCUAUAAGCUAAUAUCAUAAAUAAGGUUGUUUAAGACGUGCUUCAAAUAUCCAUAUUAACCACUAUUUUUCAAGGAAGUAUGGAAAAGUACACUCUGUCACUUUGUCACUCGAUGUCAUUCCAAAGUUAUUGCCUACUAAGUAAUGACUGUCAUGAAAGCAGCAUUGAAAUAAUUUGUUUAAAGGGGGCACUCUUUUAAACGGGAAGAAAAUUUCCGCUUCCUGGUCUUAUCAUGGACAAUUUGGGCUAGAGGCAGGAAGGAAGUGGGAUGACCUCAGGAGGUCACCUUUUCUUGAUUCCAGAAACAUAUGGGCUGAUAAACCCGGGGUGACCUCAUGAAAUGAGUUGCAGCAGAAGUUUAUUUUUUUCAGAACAAGUGAUGUUUGAUGGACCUCUGAAUCUCUUUAGGGAGACACAGAUGGCUGGGAUCCCUCCCCUGUACCCUUCUCACUGCCAGGAGAACUACGUGUGAAGGUAUUCAAGGCAGGGAGUAUACAUUGCUGUUUCCUGUUGGGCAAUGCUCCUUGACCACAUUUUGGGAAGAGUGGAUGUUAUCAUUGAGAAAACAAUGUGUCUGGAAUUAAUGGGGUUCUUAUAAAGAAGGUUCCCAGAAAAGAAUGUUCAUCCAGCCUCCUCAGAAACAGAACAUUCAAGAAAAGGACAAUCAGGAUGUCAUCAGGGAAAUGAAAAUAAAAACCACAAUGAGAUAUCACCUUAUACCAGGUAGAAUGGCUACUAUAAAAAAAUGAAGUGUCAUCAAGGAUAUAGAGAAAUUGGAACCCUUCUUCACUGCUGGAGGGAAUGGAAAAUGGUGUAGCCGUUAUGAAAAACAGUACGGAGGUUUCUCAAAAAUUAAAAAUAGAACUGCUAUAUGAUCCAGCAAUCUCACUUCUGUAUAUAUACCCAAAAUAAUUGAAAUCAGAAUUUCAAGAAAAUAUUUACACUCCCAUGUUCAUUGUGGCACUCUUCACAAUCACUGUUUCCAAAGUUAUGGAAACAACCCAAAUUUCCAUUGAAAAAUAAAUGGACAAAGAAAAUGUGCAUAUACGUACAAUGGGAUAUUAUUCAGCCUAAAAAAAGGGGGAAUCCUGUUAUUUAUGACAACAUGAAUAAACCCGGAGGCCAUUAUGCUAUGUAAAAUGAGCAAGUAACAGAAAGACAAAUACUGCCUGAUUUCAUUUAUAUGAGGUUCUAAAAUAGUCAAACUCAUAGAAGCAGAGAAUAGAACAGUGGUUCCUAGGGAAAAGGAGGAAGGGAGAAAUGAGGAAAUAGGGAGUUGUCUAAUUGGUAUAAAAUUAUAGUAUGCAAGAUGAAUUAGCUCUAAAGAUCAGCUGUAUAGCAGAGUUCGUAUAAUGAACAAUACUGUAUUAUGCACUUAACAUUUUGUUAAGAGGGUACCUCUCAUGUUAAGUGUUCUUACCAUAUACAUAUACACAAGGAAGCUUUUGGAGGUGAUGGAUAUAUUUAUUACCUUGAUUGUGGUGAUGGUUUGACAGGUAUGUGACUAUGUCUAAACUCAUCAAAUUGUAUACAUUAAAUAUAUGCAGUUUUAUAAUAUCAAUUAUGUCUGAAUGAAGCUAUAAAAAAGAAAAGACAACAAAAUUCAGUUGUCAAAACUGGAAAUAUGACCACAGUCAGAAGUGUUUGUUACUGAGUGUUUCAGAGUGUGUUUGGUUUGAGCAGGUCUAGGGUGAUUGAACAUCCCUGGGUGUGUUUCCAUGUCUCAUGUACUAGUGAAAGUAGAUGUGUGCAUUUGUGCACAUAUCCCUAUGUAUCCCUAUCAGGGCUGUGUGUAUUUGAAAGUGUGUGUGUCCGCAUGAUCAUAUCUGUAUAGAAGAGAGUGUGAUUAUAUUUCUUGAAGAAUACAUCCAUUUGAAAUGGAUGUCUAUGGCUGUUUGAGAUGAGUUCUCUACUCUUGUGCUUGUACAGUAGUCUCCCCUUAUCCCUUAUGCUUGGUGGAUACGUUCUUAGACCCCAAGUGGAUCUCUGAGACCGCAGAUGGUACCAAACCUCAUAUAUGCAAUAUUUUUUCCUAUACAUAAAUACCUAAGAUAAAGUUCAUCUUCUGAAUUAGGCACAGUAAGAGAUUAACAAUAACUAACAAUAAAAUUGAAUAGUUAUAAUAAUAUAUUGUAAUAAAAGUUAUGUGAAUGUGAUCUCUUUCUUUCUCUCUCUCAAAAUAUCUUACUGUACUGUACUCACCUAUUUUCAGACCAUAACUGACCAUGAAACCUGGGAAAGUGAAACUGUGGAUAAGUGAGGAACUAACAUACAUACAUGAUUGUUUAUCUACAGAUGUAUGCCUCAGUUUCUUAGUAUGCUUGAAAAUGUAUGAUUUUGUGUAUAUCCGUGCUACAUGUAAGUGUGGUUCUAUUCAUAUUUGAAUAUGAAUUCUGCAUAAGUGUGUUUAUUCAAGCAAAUGUACAAGGCUCUGAGAAGGAAGAUCAACAUACAACUUGGAAUAUUUCAAGGCCGAAAUAUUCAAGGCUGACAUUGGCCUCCUUCCUAUCAGUUCCCUCUCCCAGAUGGAAAUUCUAGAAAUGGCAGGUGAGGUGGACAAGCAGGGAAAGAAAUUAUAUGCAUAGAACAGAAGGAGAAGAAAGAGUAAAGUCAGGCCUCAGCCAGCCUCUUUUUAGCUCUUUAAAUCCUCUGGAUUUAAGAGGGAUAAAGGGUGGAAUAAGGAUAAAUUAAUGCCAAUUGUAAUGCCUUAAAUUUGUGUGAUACCUUACAACUUGAAACAUAUUCACAAAACUAUAUAUUUGAAUAUCUCAUUAGCUGAGUAAGGUAGCAAAUCAUAAUUAACUUUUUCCAUUUUAUUGAUGGGAAAGCUGAAGUUCAAUGAAGUAAAUUUUUCAAUAGCCCACAGAGUAGGAAAGUGACAAAACCUGAGCCUGGGCCUCCAGGUCACUCAAGGACACUUUCUUUCUUCCACACCCAAUUGCUUCAUGCUUAAAGUUGGCAAAACAGGAAGUGAAACUCCUGCAGUUUUCUGUGUGGUUGACACUAGCAAGGGUUUCUCAGUUGAAGCCAUGAAUCAUUAAGCCAAUACAUAUGCAUAUAUGUUAUACAUACCAAAUGAUUUAUUUAUAACCCUAUCUUUCCAUAAAGGACUUGAAGGAGCUUCAAACAAAGGAUAUGUGAACAAUAGGGUUAAUCAAUAAUAAGUAGAAAAUCUGGACAUAGAAUAAAAAGAGGAGAGAAAGACACCGAGAAUGAGCGUUAAUACAGUGCUUUCCAUUUUUCUGGUGUUUUGAGUAGCGUGGCUUUUGGAGAAAGCCAAAACUCAAAUUCACUCCUUAUCAACUGUGUGCCUUGGGCUCCAUUUCUCUGAGAGUCUACUUAGCUCCAAUGUAAAAUAAGAAUAGAACUAUGACUUUGUAAGGUUGCUCUAAGGAUUGAAAAUCAUGUAUUAUGUUCAAUACGGGGACACUGUCCUUAUGGGUGAGUACUCCCCUAAGACUUUAUUAAGAGGGCACUAGGAGAAGCACUGGGAGGUCUUCUCAGUAACAACACUAAAGUAAUUGCUAUUUUUCCAGCCUGUGGAACCACAGAAGUGACUGUAACUAAAAUUAGACAUUUCUUUCUGAUUCAUUCUCUACUCACGGGAUUGUCAGACCCCAGUCUUCUUCUGGACUCUAUAAACUUUUUAGAAAUCAUCAGCAGGCUCCUGGAGAAGCUUAAAUGAACUCACACAAUAUGUGACAGUGAACUCCCUGGGAGAGUGAAAACCAAAGUCUAAGCCAGUGUCUCCAUUUACUUGUGUGAUUGUGGGCAAGUCAUUCAAGUGCUUUGAGGCUCAGGUCUUAAUUCAUGAAAUGGAGGUAAUAAUACCUUGUUGGCAGACCUCACUUGGUUAAAAUGAUAAUGUUGAUAGUUACAAUAGUUACAUUUAAUUGAUCAAUUGUUUUAUGCAAGGGCUUUAUUUGUGCUAUCUCAGUUUGUCACAUCAAUGAAUUAGAAAGAUACGAAAGUAUUUCCAAUUUACAAAUGAGGAGUCUGAGUCUGGGAGUCAUUCUGUCAUGUGUCCACUGUCACCUGCUCAUUGGUGGCAGCACUGAGAUUAGGAUCUAAGUCCACUUCACCGCAGAAGCAGGGCUUCUAAAUACUGUUCUAUGGCAAGAGCACCCUGCUCUCACAAAAUGCAUAAAACUUCCUAUCUCACCAUUAUAAUUUUGACUGAUAUUAAACAAAGAGAAGUAUUAUUAUUAUUACUUGUUUUUAUUUAUAUUACAGCUGUAAGAGCCAGGAAAAAUGUGAUCUAAGUUAUGUGAUCAAAGAUUUUUUAACAGUGAACAAAUCAGGCCCACUAGAUGAUGGCCUUUCUUUGAACAACAUGCCUAGGGUUGCUCUAUCAUGUCUACAGUUGGUCUGACUUCCUGACGGGCAUCACAGACUUGUGAUUAAACACAGAGGUUAUGGGGGAAGUUCCAAAAGCUUAGGACUUUCCAGAUGGUUGGAAUAAGAUCACACACUCUGGCUGCCCUUAUGGAGAUCACCGAACUUUUCAACUCAAAGUAAAAUCUGUGGAGUAAAUGGUCGAUCAAAAGGAACCAACUAUAUUGAGCACCAUGCGUGAUCAUCUGAUCGUUACUGCUACCUUGUGAGUUAAAGGCUACUCUUCUCAUUUUAGAAAUGAGAAAAGAGAUGCCCAGAGAGGACGAGUAACUUGCCUUAGGUCACACAGCUUAUAUUAAUCACAAUAACAUUUGCCGCACCUUCUGUAUUUUUUUUAAGUUGCUAAGCUUUUGGUGCAUGUCUGGCACCGUUUUAGUUGUAUAUUAUUUCAUUUAAUUGUUAAAAUGACCUUCUGAUGCAGGUAUUUGUAGCUUUGCCAUUCCACAGAUGAAGAAACAGAUGAAAGGACUGAAUUGUUCAAUAGGAAGGAGCAGAAUCAGGAUAUGAACUUGGGUUGGCCUGAUUCUUGGGGCUGCAUUCUUUCCAUAACAUAAUUGCUUGCUGUGAUGUCCUGGGCUACUCUGCCAGGGGUGGUUAGUGGAGUGAAUGGAGAAUAAUUUAGACAAGGUCAGUAACUCCCAUGCCAUCUAGAAAUUAAAAGUUUAAAAGGCAGAGUCUGCAACUCUCCUUGAUUUCUACAGAAAUAAAGAUGAUCCCUCCUGUGACAGUGCUAAGUGACAAUUCUGAGUGUAAAUGCGCUUUUUGGCACAAAUUGUCCUGUCCUAAUAGUCUUGAUUAUAAUUAUAAAAUAAUGGGUUUCUGAAAGGCUGCAAGCAGUUCUGGGAAUGGCAAUAAAGGUUUAGAAAUGACGUGAUGUUUAUGAGAGAAGUGUUUUGUUGAAAAUUAAACUCACGUUUAGGAGAAAGGAUUGUGUUGUAUGCUCCUAGGAAACUAUCUCACUAUGUAAUUAAAUCAAAACCAGCCAGUUACCAAUUUGAGCUCUUGACUCAUACUAACAACACCCCAUUUCCCAUGGGCCAAGCAAGGCAGGACUGACCUGAAAUAACCCAGCCUGACUCUAUCCACAGCCACCCCAGGACCUUGCCCCUCCGUCUUCCUAGGGCUCGGCCGUGAGAUGCUAGUGCAUGACCCUUCCUCUUCCUGGGACUGUCCUUGUCUUUCCCUUUGGACUCUGGGAGGUCUGUUCUCCUCCUCAGAAAGGAAUAAACACUCUUUCUAUUUGUGGGAUUCCCUAGGAGACACUAUAUAAAAAUAUAGAGUUAAAAAAACUAUUUAAAAAAAAGACAACUUCAUGUCUCUACUCUGACUUCAUUCUUUUUAAGAUGGGUAACAAAGACUCUCUUCAAGGUUAGAAAAUUUUAUUUUAAUUUUUAUAGAUUUAGAGAGUGCAAAUGCAGUUUUGUUACAUGAAUAUAUUGCAUAAUGGUUUAGUCUGGGCUGUUAGCGUAACCAUCAACUGAACAGUGUACUUUGUACCUAUUAGGUACUUUCUCAUCCCUUAACCCCUUCCCACCUUUCUGAGUCCUCAAUGUCUGUUAUUUCAUUCUCCAUGUCCAUGUCUACAAAUUAUUUAGUUUCCACUCAUAAGUGAGAGCAUGGAUGGAACUGGAGAAGAGUAUUUUCUAUCCCAAGAUCGGUUCCUUGAUCUUGUGUCUCCAAAUCACUUGCUCUCUCUCUUACAUCUUUUCUAUCUUCUUCUAGCCUCUUUUUGCAAACUUCAUUUUGACAAAGAAUUCCAGGCAGUCUACAGCUGAUUUUAUUUCAAUACAACGAUUAAAAUGGAAACCAUAUAUGAAGAUGACAAAGUUGAGCAGGUCCCAAACUCUCACUUUUAAACAAAUGCUUGGCUUAAGAAUCACUUAAUGACUUUCAUUCUGCUAUCUAUGUGUCUGUGUAUCUAGGUACUAAUUAUCUAUCUUUAUGAUCUUUAUUGCUAGAAAUUCUGGUUCAAUAUCAGAGGUUAGUCCUAAGGAAUUUAUAUUUUAAAAUAUUCUCCCAGUUUUCGUGCACAGACAGAUUUGGGAAUUACUGUUAUAAUGGAAAAUGGAGAAUAACCACCCACAUUUAAUAUGGUUAUUGGUUUUGUUCUUGAGAUUUAUUGCUAAGAUUCAUGAUAGCCCAGGCAAGGUCAGAUAAUGUAUUUUUAUUUUACACUGUAUAGUUGAUUCUUCUCAAUCCCACUAGAUCAGACUCUUUGGGAUACUAGGAUUGGCCUAUUUGAUGGUGAGCUCACUACAUCCAUUUAGAUGUUGUGUCCAUGCAAUCAUUUUAGUUCUCCUAGUUUCUACCUAUCACGUUGUCAUUUUCCCUUCUUUAUCAUCCUGGGUAGCUGAGACCCCACAUAAAUAUAUACCAGAAAAAUGUUGUGGUCUUUUCUAAACUCUCUGAGGCAUCUGUUGUCAAUGUGAUGUUGUUUUUUGUUUCCAGUCCAAAAUAUAUCAAAGUAAAAUUUAACUCCACUUUUGCUAAGUAUUCAUCUUGCCUUGAGUACUAAGAUUCCAAAAAUGACUUUCCCCUCUGAAAAACACAGGAUUUCCUUGCGAAAACUUGCUGGGCCACUGCCAAUCUUCCCAGAAACUCCUUUUUCCUUAUCGUUGAGGGGAAUUGGGGAAGUGAUCACUGACGGUUGAAAUUCAGUAGUUUUGGUCUUUAAGCUGAGACCCUGAGUCUUCUGAGGAGUCUACUGCUCCCCAGUGGGAAACACCUGCUGUCAAAAUUUUCCUGCUUGCAAAGAGCACUUUUGAAAUUAAUGGCAGGGGAUGAAUAUCUGGCUAGUGCUGUGCUCAGCUGAGUUAUUAAUAGGGCCUUCUGAGUCCUCUCUACACAUCAUCUUUGGCUGAAUUAGCUGUGGUUUCAGCACCUGAGAGUCUAGCACCACUAAAGGCAGGGAAUACCUUUGCCAGUUUCUGGCAUAUUAACAGCUGAGAUCAGAUAAGUGAACAGCGAUAGAGGUAGUGAGGUUUAGGAUUCAGGUCUGCCACCGGGAGCGCACCUCUGGGCUCAGGUCUCUCAUUUGUAAAAUGGGACAUUUAGGUCAGAUCAGCAUUUUCAAAAGUGUGACAUGUUAGUAAAUAAGAUGAUUUUAUGUGGUUGACAGAUGAAUGUAUUACCUUUAGUGGUUAUAUGUUUAUUUUCAUGGUUACUUUUAUUUAUAAUAAAUUUUGUGACUAGCUAAGAAUCAAUUAUCUCUUUAAAAUAUAUUUAAGUUUAAAAUGUGGGCCAACUUAGGAAAAAAACGGGAUGAAAUGAAUUAUAUAAAAGGUAUGCAGAUUUGGAAAAAUUUUGAAGGUGUCACAAGAAAGAUUGGCAGUCAGAAAGGAAUGAACCAAACGGCUGCUGAGGGUCAGGCCAGCUCUCUGACAUUCUAGCAUGUUCACAUCUCCAGGGCUGUUUCCUUACCUAUAAAUUGUGGCAAUUGGAGUAAAUGUCCAUUCCAGGAAUUCUAUUCUAUGAUUAGAGGUGUAACUUCAUCAUCCAGAUUUUCCAGCAUCCUUAACAUGUGGUUUUAGCGUUCUAAACCUGAUGAUGCUAUAUCAAAACGGGAGACUCAUUCGUCAAGUCAUGAUGUAUCCAUGUAUUUAUAAUAUUUCCCAUGUUCCCUCAUUUCUGAAAAGGAUUAAGCUAUCAACCCCAUUGAGUUAUAGGUGAAAGGCUGUGGAAACAAGACAUUGAUAGUGAAAUGGCUCCACCACUAACAGGCUGUUGAACAAAGGCAAAUCUCUUGAUCUCUUUGCUCUUUGGUCUCUGUUUAUCUAUGAGAUAACGUUAUUUUUACGCUGUCUUCUGUGAAAGUUUUGAGAAUGAAAUGAGACAGAGCCUCCAAUAAAAUUUAGGGAAGUGCUACAUAAAUGCAAGGAGUUAUUAUGAUAACAGAUUGAAAACUCCUCCAAGGAGGAGUUUCUCUUUUGCCCCAUGUUAUAAACUCAAGAAUAUCUUCCAUUUUGCCUACAUAUUCCAAAAGCUUUUAAAUUAAGCUAUAUGUCAUUCUUACAGGAGUCUCCUCUAUUUCAGCAAUGUGUAUACUUGGUCAGUUUUAAUUAUCUUAAAGGAGAAGAAUACAGUUUCUCUAAACUCAAGCACUUUUGUGGACUAAUCCUUGCAAUUAUUCUUUCUUCUUUCCCAUACUUGACAUUUAAAGUGAUAUCUCCCAGGCUCCUACACUGUUAGUCACAGAGGUACCAUUCGACCCCUUGUGCCUCUUACCAUAUGUGAAUGCUUGUCAGUUGAGAGUAAACUUUCUUCAUAAAUUUCACAGUUGUGGAUUGAUAAAAACAGAGAACUCUGGUUCCUCAUUCCUUCCUGCUUUCUUUCUUGAAAUGCCAUUCAUGAUGGUCCCUUAUAUCACUAUAGGGCUGCUAUCAUCCUUCAUCCUUAUGCCACUGCAAAUAGCAACCAACAGUGUCCUUAGUGCCAGCACUCCCAGGCAUGCCCCUUUCCAAGCAGCAGGGUCAAGCCGCUCCCUUCCUGAGCUGUGGCAUCUGUCUCUAAAUCAUGCUUCCUCCUUGCCUGCUGCAGGCCCUUGUCUCUGCCCUUUACUUUUUCUGGCUCUUGCCACGGUUUUGAAUAAAACUCUUCCAAAUAUCUGAAGCUCAAUUCUGUUGCCAUUCUAAGCUCUCUAAAUGUCACCACAAUCUUCCUUCCUUUGCAUUUUCUUAUUGUGCACUAAGUUAGUUCUUGCUUAGUAAGUCUUGUCUUUCUCUCUGCUUUGACCUGUCAGUAUUCCAACUUCCUUAUUUUUUGAUGUUCAUUUUCUCCUUGCUCUCUUUCUUCCUUUCUUGUCUGUGAACUCCAUUAACCGCUUCUGCAUGUGACCAUUAAUGUGCCUGUCUUUCUUCUCAUGUAUUAGAGAGAACAAAAGCUUUGGGAAUCAGACAGAUCUGUGUUCUGAUCCUGUCUUAUGGUAUCUGUCUUGUUUGUCUCGGCUUAAAAUGGGGAUAAUAUCUACCUCUCAGUUUUGUUGGCAGUUCAGUACACGGAAAUAAAGUUCUCACUUUCUUUUUUCUCCUUGA